CAUGCCACUGCAGCCCAGCCUGUGUGACUGAGCCAGACCCUGUUUCUAAUACAUGAAUAUAGAAGGACUGGAUAUCUCAAUUUCAAAGUUCAGAUUUUCAGAUGAGAUUAAACAAUAAAUAAAUAAACAAGACCCAACACUAUGCUGCUCACAAGAACCACAUUUUAGAUACAGACACAACAUUUAGGCAAAAGUAUAGAUGUAAAUGUGCCAUGCAAAUACUAAUCCUAAAAGAGUUGGUAUGCCCAUAUUAAUAUUAGAUAAAGUGGUCUUCAGAACAGGAGUACUGCCAAAGAUAAAGGUGUCGAGUCAUAAUCAAAAUAGGCCAGUUCAUAAAAUUAACAAUCUUAAAUGGGUGAACCUAGUGAAACUUCAAAAUGUGUGAAACAGAUAUCAACAGAGUAAAGGUGACGAUCAUCAGAUCUACUUUUCAAGUGUAUGUGGAACAUUAAUCAAGAUAGAUUAAAUACUGGACCAUAAAAUAAUUCUCAAUAAAUAUAAAAGGAUUUAAAUCAUAGACAGUUUGUACUCUGAGCAAAAUAGGACUAAAUUAAGUCAAUAACAAAAAUAUAUUCAGAAAAACCUUAAUAUUUGGCAAUUGAGCAAAUAACUUUUAAAUAAAAAUGGAUAUAGGAAUUCUCAGAUCUAUAUUUAAAUUUUUAAAUUGUGUUAAAAUUUUAACUUUAAGUAUAUAAUUCAGUAGCAUUAAGUACAUUCCCAGUUUUGUACAACCAGCAUCUUCAUUUCUAUCACAAACAGAAAUAAAGUACCCAUUAAACAAUAACCCAGCAUUGCUACCUCUCCCCAGUCUCUGGGAAACACUAAUCUUCAUUCUAUUUUCACAAAUUUGCCUAUUCUAGAUAUUUCAUAUCAGUGGAAUCAUACAACAUCUGUCCUUUCGUGUCUGGCUUACUUCACUCAGCAUCAUAUUUCCAAGUUUCACCCAUGUUGCAUGUAUCAGAACUUCAUCCUCUUUAAUGGCUGAAUAAUAUUCUAUUAUUUAUGUAUCAUAUUUGUGUAUCCAUUCAUUUGUUGAUGGACACGGGUUGUCCGUGCCUUUUGGCUAUAACGAAUAACGCUGCAAUUAACUUGGGUGUAAAAAUAUCUGUUCCAGACCCUGCUGUCAAUUUUUUUGUGUGUGAAUAAUACCUAGGAGUGGAAUUUCUGUUUCUCUGUGUGAUUCUGUGAGGAACCACCAAAUUGUUUUCCACAGCAAGUGCAUCAUUUUCUAUUCCUAGCAGUCAGUUCACGAGGGCUCCAAUUUCUCCACCUCUUUAGCAACAUUUAUUUUCUGUGUCGUUGUUAUGAAAGCCUUACUAGUGGAUGCAAAGUGGCAUCUCGUUUUGAUUUUGUCUUGCAUUUUAUUAAUGAAUAAUGGUGCUUAGCAUCUUUUCUUGUCCUUCAUAGACAUUUAUGUAUCUUCUUUGGAGAAAUGUCUAUUCAAGUCCUUUGCCUAUUUUUUAAUUGGGAUGUUAGAAAUUCUGUUGUUGAGUUGUGGGAUAUUAAGCUUUUAUCAGAUACACACUUUGAUUUUAUCAGAUACGUAUUUUCUCACAUACUAUGGGUUGUCUUUUCAGUCCCUUGAUGGUAUCCUUUGAUGCAUAAAGGUUUUUUAUUUUGAUUAAAUCUAAUUUAUGAGUAUUUUCUUUUGUUAUCUGUGCUUUUCUGUCAUACUUCAAAAUACACUUAAAACUCAAAGGUCAUAAAGGUUUACCUUGUGUUUUCUUCUAAGAGUUACAUAUUUUUAGUCCUUACAUUUAAGUCUUUUAUUAAUUUAUAAUUAAUUUUUGUAUAUACUGCAAGGUAGGGUUCUAACUUCUCUCUUGUGCACUGACAUCCAGCUGUUGAAGAGACUGUUCUUUCCUCCCUUGACUAGACUUGGCCACCUUGUUGAACAGUCAUUGACCAUAUAUGUGAGGACUAAUUUGUAGGAUCUCAAAUCUAUUCUAUUCUAUUGGUCUAAAAGUCUAUUGGUCUUAUGCCAGUACCACACUCUCUUGAUUACUGUAGAUUUGUAAUAGGUUGUGAAACUGAAAAAUGUGAGUUUUCCAAUAUUCUUUUUCAAGACUGUUUUUGUCUGUCAGAUCCUUUGAAUUUUUGUAUGAAUUUUAGAAUGAGUUUCUUUGUUUCUGCAAAGAUGCCUUUGGGAUUUUGAUGGUAUUGCAUUGAAUCUGUAGAUUACUUUAGAUGGUAUUGUCAUCUUAACAAUAUUGUCUUACAACCCGUGAACACAGAAUGUCUUUCCAGUUAUUUCCACUCUCUUUAGUUUUUUUCAGCAAAGUUUUGUGUAUACCACCAUGAUUAGAUUUAUGCCUGAAUAACUUAUUCUUUGAUGCUAUUAUAAAUGGAAUUUUUUAAAUGUUUUCAUAGUUCUUUACAACUAUAUAGAAAUAUAGCUCAUUUGCAUAUGUUUGUUUUGCAUCCUGCCUCUUUUAUUAGUUAUAAUCGGUUUUGUGUUUUGUUUGGAGCUUUAUACACAUAAGAUCAUGUGUAGAUAUAAUUUUACUUCUAUUUUUUAUUUCUAAUUUAGAUGCCUUUUAUUUCUUUGUCUCGCCUGAUUGCUCUGGGUAGAACUGCCAAUGCUAUGUUGAAUACAAGUGGCAAAUGCACCAUCCUUGUCUUGUUCUAGGUGUUAGGAAAACAGCUUUCAGUGUUUCAUCAUUGAUCAUGAUAUUAACUGUUGGGUUUUUAUACAUCCCAUUGUCAGGUUGCAGAAGUUCCCUUCUAUGCCUAGUUUAUUGAGUAUUUUUAUUAUAGAAGGGUAUUGUAUUUCAUCAAUGUUUUUUCUUCAUCAAUUGAAAUAAUCAUGUGCGUAUUCAUUUUACUGUUACAGUACAUUAUACUGAUUGAUUUUUUUAUAUGUUGAGCCACCCUUGCAUUUUGGGGAUAAAUCUCACAGGGUGAUAGUUUACAAUCCUUUGAUUAUACAGUAUUGCUGCUAGUAUUUUGGUAGUAUUGCUAGUAUUUUGCAGAGAUUUUUGCUUAUAUAUUCAUAAGGGAUAUUGUGCUGUAGUUCUCUUUUUUGUGCUCUCCUUGGCUUUGGUAUAAGGAUAAUGCUAUUAUCAAAAAAUGAAUUAGCAAGUAUUCCUUCUUCACAUAUUUUGUCAGAAGACUUUGAGAAGAAAUGGUAUUAAUUCUUCUUUAAAUGUUAGGUUGACUCACCAGUUAAUGCAGCUAUUUGGUCAUAAAUGUUUCUUUGUUAAUCGCUUUCGAUUACUAAUUCAAUCUCUUAGGUUAUAGGUCUAUUCAGAUUUUCUCUUUCUUCUUGAACCACUUUAGUAGUUUGUGUCUUUCUAGCAAUUCGUCCAUUUCAUCCAGGGCACCUAAUUUGUUGUUAGACAGUUGUUCACAGUAUACUCCUGUAAUCCUUUUGUAUUUCUGUAAAGUUGGUAGUAAUGGCUCUGCUUUCAUUUAUUAUUUUAAUAAUUAGUCUUCCAUCUUUUGCUCAGUCAAUAUAGUGAAAGGCUUGAUCUUUCAAAUAAUCUAUGUUUAUUUAUUCUACUGCUCUCCAACAUUCUAUUUUAUUGAUUUAUGCUCUAAUUAUGCUCUUUAUUAUUUCUUUCCUUCUGCUAGCUUUGGAUUUAGUCUUUUUUUGUUUUCUUCCAUUGCCUUUAGGUAUAGAAUGAGGAUAUUGAUUUGAGAUUUCUUCUUAAAUGUAGUUGUUUAUAUCCAUACAUUUUCCCUUGAACUCUACUUUCACUGCAUUCAAUAAGUUUUGGUAUGUUUUGUUUUUAUUUUGUCUCAAGAUAUUUUAUAAUUUUGCUUGUGAUUUAUUUUUUCACUCACUGGUAGUUUAAGACUGUAUUGUUUAAUUUUCACAUUUUUGUGAAUUUUCCAGUUUUCACUUAUUUAUCUGUUGUUUCUUCCAUUGUGGUUGUAAAUUAUAUUUUGUAUGAUUUCAAACUUUUAAAAAUGAUUAGGACAUAUUUUGUGGACGAAGAUAUGGCCUAUCCUAGAGAAAGUUCCAUAUACACUUGAAAAGAAUGUAUGUUCUGCUGUUGUUGGAUGGACUGUUCUGUAUAUGUAUAUUAGCUCUCAAUGGUUUAUACUGUUGUUUAAGUCUUGUAUUUCUCAUAAAGCUUCUGUCUGGUUUUUCUAUCCAUUAAUUAAAAUGAGGUAUUGAAGUGUCCAACUGUUACUAUAGAACUGUGGGUUUAUCCUUUCGAUCCUGUUAAUUAUUUCAGCUUUACUGAGGUGUAAUAGAGAAAAUUGUACAUGUGAUGCGUUUAUAUGCACAUUCUGAAAUGAUUACCAAAAUGAAGUCAAUUAACAUGUUAAUUACCUCACAGAAUAGUUACCUUUUUGUGUGCAUGCCUGGGAUAAGAAAACUUAACUCUAUCCCCUGUGACUGCAGAGUGGCCAUUCCAGCUGCUCCAGGCUCCAGCAGAGGAAGACCGGGUCAGGUGGCACCAGCAGGAGGGCCCUCAGGUCUGGCGCGCACGCAUUCCAGAGGCCACCCAGACCAUGCUCCGCCGCCUGGGCGCCCAAGCUGCAGUCGCCCUCUGUGUGCAGGCAGCAGCUGCCUGGCAACCUCCGAGCCCGCUCGCGCUCCCAGCAUCGCAGAACCAGGGCCAGGUGUCCCAGUGGCUGCAGCCAAGCCAGGCAUUCUGCCCAGCGGCGGCUGCACAGGAGCAGAACCGAGAACCCGCCGCUCAACCCCACACGGGGUGACUGCCGAGUGCCCAUGCCAGCGGCCCCAAUCCCCCUCAGGUGGAGGAGUGGGCGGGAGGCACGACCUGGGGGCCCUCAGGCUGGGCGCGCUGGCGAUCCCGAGGCCGACCAGGCCAUGCACCUCCAGCCCGCCUGGGCACCCAAGCUGCAGCCGCCUUCUGUGUGCAGGCAGCAGCCUCCAGGCAACUCUCGAGCCCGCCCGCACUCCCCACAUCUCAGAACCAGGGCCAGAUGUCCCUGUGGCUGCGGCCAAGCCAGGCGGUCUGUCCUGCAGCAGCUGCACAGGGGCGGGAACCGGCCCUCAGCCCCAUCCCCGGUGGUUGCAGAGGGCCCCUGGCUAGAGGUCUCGAGCUCUGGCAGAGGAGGAGCCGGGUGGGGGCAGGGUCUGGCGGGCUCUCAGGCCAGGGGCACUCGCGAUCCAGAGGCCGCCCAGGCCAUGCUCCACCACCUGGGCGCCCAGCUACAGGCGCCAGGCAACUCCCAAGCUGGCUGGCGCGCCCAGCCUCGCAGAACCGGGGCUAGAUGUCGCUGUGGCUGCGGCCAAGCCAGGCGGUCUGCCCGCGGCGGCUGCACCGGGGCAGGAACCGACCCUCAGCCCCAUCCCCGGUGGCUGCGGAGAGCCCCUGCCAGCGGCCCCAUCUCUCUUCGGAGGAGGAGAGGAGCGGGAGUCACGGCCAGGCGGGCCCUCAGGCGGGAAGGGAUGCGCGCCUGCGAUUCCGGGAUGUCCUGCGCGAGCCCAGGAGAACCCGCAAGCCAGCGGCGCCUGCGCCCGAGCUGCAGCCGCCCUCUGCCGUCCACGCGAGCUCGAGAGCGGCUCCCGGAGUCCGGGCUAGCGCCGAGCUGCAGGCGCGCGCCUAACCGCUUUGCUGGGCUCACGCGGUCUGAGAGGUCGGAGCGCCCAACUGCUGGCACGCGAGUAACGGCUUAG